GCCGGCCCAUGACUGAGCCCCGCCGCCGCCGGCCGAGGAAUGGGCUCCGGGCUCUGGUAGGAAGCGCUGGGAGCGGGGGGCGCUUUUAAAACACCGAUCUGGGUUUUUUAAAAACCUCCUUUGAAAAAAUAAUGGCAAACUCGACGGGGAAGGCGCCUCCGGACGAGCGGAGAAAGGGACUCGCUUUCCUGGACGAGCUGCGGCAGUUCCACCACAGCAGAGGGUCGCCUUUUAAAAAAAUCCCUGCGGUGGGUGGGAAGGAGCUGGAUCUUCACGGUCUCUACACCAGAGUCACUACUUUAGGCGGAUUCGCGAAGGUUUCUGAGAAGAAUCAGUGGGGAGAAAUUGUUGAAGAGUUCAACUUUCCCAGAAGUUGUUCUAACGCUGCCUUUGCUUUAAAACAGUAUUACUUGCGUUACCUAGAAAAGUACGAGAAAGUUCAUCAUUUUGGGGAGGAUGAUGAUGAGGUACCACCAGGCAAUCCAAAGCCACAGCUUCCUAUUGGUGCAAUUCCAUCUUCCUACAAUUACCAGCAACACAGUGUGUCGGAUUAUCUGCGUCAAAGUUAUGGGCUGUCCAUGGACUUUAAUUCGCCAAAUGAUUAUAAUAAAUUGGUGCUUUCACUGUUAUCUGGACUCCCAAAUGAAGUGGACUUUGCUAUUAACGUAUGCACUCUCCUAUCAAAUGAAAGCAAGCACGUCAUGCAACUUGAAAAAGAUCCUAAAAUCAUCACUUUACUACUUGCUAAUGCCGGGGUGUUUGACGACACUUUAGGAUCCUUUUCCACUGUAUUUGGAGAAGAAUGGAAAGAGAAGACUGAUAGAGACUUCGUUAAGUUUUGGAAAGACAUCGUUGAUGAUAAUGAAGUUCGUGACCUCAUUUCUGACAGAAACAAGUCUCAUGAAGGUACAUCAGGAGAAUGGAUUUGGGAGUCUUUAUUUCAUCCACCUCGAAAGCUGGGCAUUAACGAUAUUGAAGGACAGCGGGUACUUCAGAUUGCAGUGAUUUUGAGAAAUCUUUCCUUUGAGGAGGGCAAUGUUAAGCUCUUGGCAGCUAAUCGUACCUGUCUUCGUUUCCUAUUACUUUCUGCACAUAGUCAUUUUAUUUCUUUAAGGCAAUUAGGCCUUGACACAUUAGGAAAUAUUGCAGCUGAGCUUUUACUGGACCCUGUUGAUUUCAAAACUACUCAUCUGAUGUUUCAUACUGUUACAAAAUGUCUAAUGUCAAGGGAUAGAUUUUUAAAGAUGAGAGGCAUGGAAAUUUUGGGAAAUCUUUGCAAAGCAGAAGAUAAUGGUGUUUUAAUUUGUGAAUAUGUGGAUCAGGAUUCCUACAGAGAGAUCAUUUGUCAUCUCACUUUACCUGAUGUGCUGCUUGUAAUCUCAACACUCGAGGUGCUAUACAUGCUCACGGAAAUGGGAGAUGUUGCUUGCACAAAAAUUGCAAAAGUAGAAAAGAGCAUAGACAUGUUAGUGUGUCUGGUUUCUAUGGAUAUUCAGAUGUUUGGCCCUGAUGCACUAGCUGCGGUAAAACUCAUUGAACACCCAAGUUCCAGUCAUCAAAUGUUAUCUGAAAUUAGGCCACAAGCUAUAGAGCAAGUCCAAACCCAGACUCAUGUAGCAUCUGCCCCAGCUUCCAGAGCAGUUGUAGCGCAGCAUGUUGCUCCACCUCCAGGAAUAGUGGAAAUAGAUAGUGAGAAGUUUGCUUGUCAGUGGCUAAAUGCUCAUUUUGAAGUAAAUCCAGAUUGUUCUGUUUCUCGAGCAGAAAUGUAUUCUGAAUACCUCUCGACUUGCAGUAAAUUAGCUCGUGGUGGAAUCCUAACAUCAACUGGAUUUUAUAAAUGUCUUAGAACGGUCUUUCCAAAUCAUACAGUGAAGAGAGUGGAGGAUUCCAGUAGCAAUGGGCAGGCACAUAUUCAUGUGGUAGGAGUAAAACGGAGGGCUAUACCACUUCCCAUUCAGAUGUACUAUCAGCAGCAACCAGUUUCUACUUCUGUUGUUCGUGUUGAUUCUGUUCCUGAUGUAUCUCCUGCUCCUUCACCUGCAGGAAUCCCUCAUGGAUCACAAACCAUAGGAAACCAUUUUCAGAGGACUCCUGUUGCCAACCAAUCUUCAAAUCUGACUGCAACACAAAUGUCUUUUCCUGUACAAGGUGUUCAUACUGUGGCACAAACUGUUUCAAGAAUUCCACAAAAUCCUUCACCUCAUACCCACCAGCAACAAAAUGCUCCAGUGACUGUCAUUCAAAGUAAAGCUCCAAUUCCUUGUGAAGUUGUUAAGGCUACAGUUAUCCAGAAUUCCAUACCCCAGACAGGAGUUCCUGUUAGUAUUGCUGUUGGAGGAGGACCUCCACAGAGUUCUGUUGUUCAGAAUCAUAGUACAGGGCCACAACCUGUUACAGUUGUGAAUUCUCAGACAUUGCUUCACCAUCCAUCUGUAAUUCCACAGCAGUCUCCAUUACACACAGUGGUACCAGGACAGAUCCCUUCAGGCACUCCUGUUACAGUAAUUCAACAAGCUGUCCCACAGAGUCAUAUGUUUGGCAGAGUACAGAACAUACCAGCAUGUACUUCUACAGUUUCACAGGGUCAACAGUUAAUCACCACAUCACCCCAACCUGUGCAAACUUCAUCUCAACAGACAUCAGCUGGUAGCCAGUCACAAGAUACUGUUAUCAUAGCACCCCCACAGUAUGUAACAACUUCUGCAUCCAAUAUUGUCUCAGCAACUUCAGUACAGAAUUUUCAGGUAGCUACAGGACAAAUGGUUACUAUUGCUGGUGUCCCAAGUCCACAAGCCUCAAGGGUAGGGUUUCAGAACAUUGCACCAAAACCUCUCCCUUCUCAGCAAGUUUCAUCUACAGUGGUACAGCAGCCUAUUCAACAACCACAGCAGCCAACCCAACAAAGCGUAGUGAUUGUAAGCCAGCCAGCUCAACAAGGUCAAACUUAUGCACCAGCCAUUCACCAAAUUGUUCUUGCUAAUCCAGCAGCUCUUCCAGCUGGUCAGACAGUUCAGCUAACUGGACAACCUAACAUAACUCCAUCUUCUUCACCAUCACCUGUCCCAGCUACUAAUAACCAAGUCCCUACUGCCAUGUCGUCGUCCUCUACCCCUCAAUCACAGGGACCACCUCCUACUGUCAGUCAAAUGUUAUCUGUGAAAAGGCAGCAACAGCAGCAACAUUCACCAGCACCCCCACCACAGCAGGUACAAGUACAAGUUCAGCAGCCCCAACAAGUACAGAUGCAAGUUCAACCUCAACAGUCGAAUGCAGGAGUUGGUCAGCCUGCCUCUGGUGAGUCGAGUCUGAUUAAACAGCUUCUGCUUCCGAAACGUGGUCCUUCAACACCAGGUGGUAAGCUUAUUCUCCCAGCUCCACAGAUUCCUCCCCCUAAUAAUGCAAGAGCUCCUAGCCCUCAGGUGGUCUAUCAGGUGGCCAGUAACCAAGCCGCAGGUUUUGGAGUGCAGGGGCAAACUCCAGCUCAGCAGCUAUUGGUUGGGCAGCAAAAUGUUCAGUUGGUCCCAAGUGCAAUGCCACCCUCAGGGGGAGUACAAACUGUGCCCAUUUCGAACUUACAAAUAUUGCCAGGUCCACUGAUCUCAAAUAGCCCAGCAACCAUUUUCCAAGGGACUUCUGGCAACCAGGUAACCAUAACAGUUGUGCCAAAUACGAGUUUUGCACCUGCAACUGUGAGUCAGGGAAAUGCAACUCAGCUCAUUGCUCCAGCAGGAAUUACCAUGAGCGGAACGCAGACAGGAGUUGGACUUCCAGUACAAACGCUUCCAGCCACUCAAGCAUCUCCUGCUGGACAAUCAUCAUGUACUACUGCUACUCCCCCAUUCAAAGGUGAUAAAAUAAUUUGCCAAAAGGAGGAGGAAGCAAAGGAAGCAACAGGUUUACAUGUUCAUGAACGUAAAAUUGAAGUCAUGGAGAACCCGUCCUGCCGACGAGGAGCCACAAACACCAGCAAUGGGGAUACAAAGGAAAAUGAAAUGCAUGUGGGAAGUCUUUUAAAUGGGAGAAAGUACAGUGACUCAAGUCUACCUCCUUCAAACUCAGGGAAAAUUCAAAGUGAGACUAAUCAGUGCUCACUAAUCAGUAAUGGGCCAUCAUUGGAAUUAGGUGAGAAUGGAGCAUCUGGGAAACAGAACUCAGAACAAAUAGACAUGCAAGAUAUCAAAAGUGAUUUGAGAAAACCGCUAGUUAAUGGAAUCUGUGAUUUUGAUAAAGGAGAUGGUUCUCAUUUAAGCAAAAACAUUCCAAAUCAUAAAACUUCCAAUCAUGUAGGAAAUGGUGAGAUAUCUCCAAUGGAACCACAAGGGACUUUAGAUAUCACUCAGCAAGAUACUGCCAAAGGUGAUCAACUAGAAAGAAUUUCUAAUGGACCUGUAUUAACUUUGGGUGGUUCAUCUGUGAGCAGUAUACAGGAGGCUUCAAAUGCGGCAACACAGCAAUUUAGUGGUACUGAUUUGCUUAAUGGACCUCUAGCUUCAAGUUUGAAUUCAGAUGUGCCUCAGCAACGCCCAAGUGUAGUUGUCUCACCACAUUCUACAACCUCUGUUAUACAGGGACAUCAAAUCAUAGCAGUUCCCGACUCAGGAUCAAAAGUAUCCCAUUCUCCUGCCCUAUCAUCUGACGUUCGGUCUACAAAUGGCACAGCAGAAUGCAAAACUGUAAAGAGGCCAGCAGAGGAUACUGAUAGGGAAACAGUCGCAGGAAUUCCAAAUAAAGUAGGAGUUAGAAUUGUUACAAUCAGUGACCCCAACAAUGCUGGCUGCAGCGCAACAAUGGUUGCUGUGCCAGCAGGAGCAGAUCCAAGCACUGUAGCUAAAGUAGCAAUAGAAAGUGCUGUUCAGCAAAAGCAACAGCAUCCACCAACAUAUGUACAGAAUGUGGUCCCGCAGAACACUCCUAUGCCACCUUCACCAGCUGUACAAGUGCAGGGCCAGCCUAACAGUUCUCAGCCUUCUCCAUUCAGUGGAUCCAGUCAGCCUGGAGAUCCAAUGAGAAAACCUGGACAGAACUUCAUGUGUCUGUGGCAGUCUUGUAAAAAGUGGUUUCAGACACCCUCACAGGUUUUCUACCAUGCAGCAACUGAACAUGGAGGAAAAGAUGUAUAUCCAGGGCAGUGUCUUUGGGAAGGUUGUGAGCCUUUUCAGCGACAGCGGUUUUCUUUUAUUACCCACUUGCAGGAUAAGCACUGUUCAAAGGAUGCCCUACUUGCAGGAUUAAAACAAGAUGAACCAGGACAAGCAGGAAGUCAGAAGUCUUCUACCAAGCAGCCAACUGUAGGGGGCACAAGCUCAACUCCUAGAGCACAAAAGGCCAUUGUGAAUCAUCCCAGUGCUGCACUUAUGGCUCUGAGGAGAGGAUCAAGAAACCUUGUCUUUCGAGAUUUUACAGAUGAAAAAGAGGGACCAAUAACUAAACACAUCCGACUAACAGCUGCCUUAAUAUUAAAAAAUAUUGGUAAAUAUUCAGAAUGUGGUCGCAGAUUGUUAAAGAGACAUGAAAAUAACUUAUCAGUGCUAGCCAUUAGUAACAUGGAAGCUUCCUCCACCCUUGCCAAAUGCCUUUAUGAACUUAAUUUUACAGUUCAGAGUAAGGAACAAGAAAAAGACUCAGAAAUGCUGCAGUGAAAAAUAAUUCCACUUACACAGUGGGGGACUCAAAGUCAGCCACAUUUCACAUACUGUUACUGAAGAAAGCACCAAGUCUUAAUGGAACAAAGACCAUAGAAUGAAUUAUUUUAUCUCCUCCCAUGAUGCUGAGAGGAAGCUUCGUAUUCUGAUCUCUGAGUGAAUCCCUUUGUUCUCUGUUUAAAAAAAUCUAAAAAGAAAAAGGAAAAAAAAAAAAGAACUGCUGUGGGAUUGUCAACCAGCUUAUCUGCAGGAUGUUUCAGAUCUGAUAAAUCCUGAUGGAAACUGGUAUGAUCAGAAUUCAGUACCAUCCACAUUGGAAUAUACAUGGAAUAUUGUAAAACCUACAUGAGCAGAUGAAAUAGAAGCAUUAAAUAUUUUUAUCUAUAUCCAAAAAGGAGCACAUUUUUAUAUUUACAAAACCGUUUAAGCUGGUUUGAAUAAUUUAAAAAAGUUUCAGCACACCUAUACCCCCGAUCUCAGAGGGGGCCACCAAUAUCUAGCUAUGGAUCGUGUGUUUUGUUUAGAAAUCAGUAGCUUGGUUUUCUUACUUGAGCCAAUAUAUUUUCACUUAUUUAUUAUCAUAAAAAUUUACCAGUCUGAAUAGAUCUUGUAAAUAUUUGUGAAUAGAAUGAAUACCUUUCAUGCCACUGCAGCCACUGGAAAUACAUUCUGUGGUGUCCUAGAAGCAUUAUUGGUAGGUUCUAAAGUUUUCUAGACUUUCCUGUCAAUUGUAAGUAAUUGUGAUAUAUUCUAUGCAGUGGAUGAAUGUUCUUUAAAUUUGUGUAAAUACUUCUGCAAAGGUACUGAUGCUGUAAAGUCAAAACAGUUUUGUGGAACUGUGAUUUUUUUUUCUUUUUUCUUUUUUUUUUUCUUUUUUUUUUUGUAUUAUACACCUUGUAGAACUCAUUUUGCUGGCUGAAAGAGUAUGGAAUAAUAUAUCUCAUGUCAUUUUUUAGAAGAAAAACUAUUUGAAGGUAUUUUUUGGUUUUCCUUAACAUGUAUCCACUGUAAACGUUUGUCGUGUACAAGCUCAGAGCUUGGACAGAAUUUUUUGUAUUUGUAAAUUGGUUUAAAUACAUGGAAUUUUAUACAGGUUUUCUCCUGUGUUAUAUAUGCAUUAUGUGCAGGUAUGAUAUUUUCUUCACUACUUUUUCUAUCUUAAUAUAGUGUGGAAUUUUAUUGUAUUAUUCUUCCAUUCUUAAUACUGUACCACAUUCCUGCUCAGAAACUGCUCACUUCCUUAAAUUGUCUUUUUUCCCCCAGCGUGAAAUGUAUCCAUUUAUAACUGCCUAUUGCCUGUUCUAUUAGCAUCCAAAAAUGUGGAAGGCCUCCCAACCACCAUUUCUGCUGUGUCCUUAGGAUGUGCAGUAAAAAAUAUAGACCUAACAGUUUAUGUUAUAGAAUGGCUUUAUUUACUUUGGUGACUGUUUAUAGUUUUUAAAUAAAAGACUGAACAUUUUCUUGAGUCCUUCAUUUCUGAGUAUGCUUAAGACAUCUUAAAAAUAUAGAGAGAAUUCUAAAUUCAGCUGAAGGCAAGGUAUAACGGUCACCUACCUAUUUGAUUAUAUGUUGAUUGAUAACAUAUUAAAUAGAGAACAAAUAAGAGAGGUCCUUUACAUGACAAAUUUGCAUGAAAUAAGCAGAUUAACCAAGUAUUUAUUUUUCAUCUUGUUAUAAUGCAGAGCAAAUGUAGAGAACAGCAAAUGAUUGAUGCAGUUAAAGCUCAAUAUGCCUUUUUUUACUGGAUACUGUACAUUUGGCUAAAAGCUUUUAUUGUUUGAUGUUGUGUUUCUUGACUGUUUAUUCAGAAUCACAGUGUAUCCAAAUCUUCAGCUUGAAUUUGGAGGCAGAUUCUUAGAGUGAAAAAGCCUCAGUUUCCAUAUUAAAAAUGUUUUAAAUAUUUUGAUUGAAUUAGUACCAAUGUAAAAUCUAGUUUCUUCCUGAAGGAGGAUCCCUGGCGCUGUCCUGCCAUGUCUCAAAGGAAUGUUUGAGAAACUUCAUCUAAUAUUAGUUAUAAGGUUGUGGAAUUUAUGCUUGGCCCACCUUCCAAGACUGGCACUGCCCAACAGACACCGCUGAAAUCAUGUGGGUAUCCCUAGGAUGGCCUUCAGAGCCCUCAAACUUACAAGCACCUGGUAGUUGACAUCAUAUGGGGAAUUUUCUAUUCACCGUACUUAUCCAAAAAUCUCUUUUAAAAAGUAAAUUUGUGCAACAACGUUUAUUUGAAAGAUAAUGUCUUCUCAAAAUCAGAAACUGCAGUGGUAAUUAAAUUAAUAGAAAAGAGAACAAACUGCAGGUUUAGAAAAAUGGUUUUCAUAUUCACCAUUCUUCCACCUCAUUGAAUUGCAUGCUGUAGUUCUAGCUUUUCUGCUAUAAUAUGUAAAUAUGACUGUAGCCUUUUAAGCUUCAGUCUCAGCAGAGAAUUUCCUAAAUGCGUUUGACCUAAUGAAACUGAUCAUGGCUUCCCACUUAGGUUUUUCUUCUUAUAGCUUUAUAGAACUAUAUAAUAAUAUGGACUUGCUGUGUAAUGGAAUUAAAGUGCUUUUGCACAAUAAGUUCUGCAAAACCCUCUCAUUCAUGAAAAGGUGCUCCUUGCUAGACAGAAACUUGCUGAUUUACAGUAUUGUUAUUUUUGUCUAAAGUUCUGUAAAUACAUGCUUUAAUGUUAUCUUUGAGAAAUCUAUGUAAAUAAUAUAGUCUACAACAUAGAGACUGUAUAAUUCUGUGUUAUAUAUGUGCCUAGUGCUCUGUUGGCACUCAAUAAAUUUUAAGUAACAAAAUUGAUAAUCAUAUAGCGAAGGCAUAUUUUUCUUCCAAGCUCAAGUCAGGAUUGUGACUAUAUAUUAAUGAGACUCAGUAAUCCAACCCACACCUGAGAACUCGUCUCAUUACUUUAUAGUCAUGUCAUGUAUGUUUUUUUAACCAUGAAAUGACAAUAAAAUGAUUUUUAAAAUGA